AGCACAGAAGGAGGAAGGACAGCACACCUGACAGCCCUGCUCAGGAAGUCUCUGGAUCCUAGGCUCAUCUCCACAGGGGAGAACACACAGACAGCAGAGACCAUGGGACCCCUCUCAGCCCCUCCCUGCACUCAGCACAUCACCUGGAAGGGGCUCCUGCUCACAGCAUCACUUUUAAACUUCUGGAACCUGCCCACCACUGCCCAAGUAAUAAUUGAAGCCAAGCCACCCAAAGUUUCCGAGGGGAAGGAUGUUCUUCUACUUGUCCACAAUUUGCCCCAGAAUCUUACUGGCUACAUCUGGUACAAAGGGCAAAUGACGGACCUCUACCAUUACAUUACAUCAUAUGUAGUACACGGUCAAAUUAUAUAUGGGCCUGCCUACAGUGGACGAGAAACAGUAUAUUCCAAUGCAUCCCUGCUGAUCCAGAAUGUCACACAGGAGGAUGCAGGAUCCUACACCUUACACAUCAUAAAGCGAGGCGAUGGGACUGGAGGAGUAACUGGAUAUUUCACUGUCACCUUAUACUCGGAGACUCCCAAGCCCUCCAUCUCCAGCAGCAACUUAAACCCCAGGGAGGUCAUGGAGGCUGUGCGCUUAAUCUGUGAUCCUGAGACUCCGGAUGCAAGCUACCUGUGGUUGCUGAAUGGUCAGAACCUCCCUAUGACUCACAGGUUGCAGCUGUCCAAAACCAACAGGACCCUCUAUCUAUUUGGUGUCACAAAGUAUAUUGCAGGACCCUAUGAAUGUGAAAUACGGAACCCAGUGAGUGCCAGCCGCAGUGACCCAGUCACCCUGAAUCUCCUCCCGAAGCUGCCCAUGCCUUACAUCACCAUCAACAACUUAAACCCCAGGGAGAAGAAGGAUGUGUUAGCCUUCACCUGUGAACCUAAGAGUCGGAACUACACCUACAUUUGGUGGCUAAAUGGUCAGAGCCUCCCGGUCAGUCCGAGGGUAAAGCGACCCAUUGAAAACAGGAUACUCAUUCUACCCAGUGUCACGAGAAAUGAAACAGGACCCUAUCAAUGUGAAAUACGGGACCGAUAUGGUGGCAUCCGCAGUAACCCAGUCACCCUGAAUGUCCUCUAUGGUCCAGACCUCCCCAGAAUUUACCCUUCAUUCACCUAUUACCGUUCAGGAGAAAACCUCGACUUGUCCUGCUUUGCGGACUCUAACCCACCGGCAGAGUAUUCUUGGACAAUUAAUGGGAAGUUUCAGCUAUCAGGACAAAAGCUCUUUAUCCCCCAAAUUACUACAAAUCAUAGCGGGCUCUAUGCUUGCUCUGUUCGUAACUCAGCCACUGGCAAGGAAAUCUCCAAAUCCAUGAUAGUCAAAGUCUCUGGUCCCUGCCAUGGAAACCAGACAGAGUCUCAUUAAUGGCUGCCACAAUAGAGACACUGAGAAAAAGAACAGGUUGAUACCUUCAUGAAAUUCAAGACAAAGAAGAAAAAAACUCAAUGUUAUUGGACUAAAUAAUCAAAAGGAUAAUGUUUUCAUAAUUUUUUAUUGGAAAAUGUGCUGAUUCUUGGAAUGUUUUAUUCUCCAGAUUUAUGAACUUUUUUUCUUCAGCAAUUGGUAAAGUAUACUUUUGUAAACAAAAAUUGAAACAUUUGCUUUUGCUCUCUAUCUGAGUGCCCCAGAAUUGGGAAACUAUUCAUGAGUAUUCAUAGGUUUAUGGUAAUAAAGUUAUUUGCACAAGUUCA